GAGCCACCAUGCCCAGCCAAAUCUAGGGCUGGAACAUGGCUGCAGCAUAUAAAUAGAAUUGAAUUCCAUAGUUUUGUUAACCCUGUUUUUUGUUUGUUUGUAGUUGUUGCUGUUUUUGAGACAGAGUCUCGCUCUGUCGCCUAGGCUGGAGUGCAGUGGUGCAAUCUCGGCUCACUGCAGACUCUGCCUCCCGGGUUCAAACUGUUCUCCUGCCUCAGCCUCCCAAGUAGGUGGGACUACAGGCGCCCACCACCACACCCGGCUAAUUUUUGUAUUUUAUUAGAGACAGGGUUUCACCAUAUUGGCCAGGCUGGUCUGGAACUCCUGACCUUGUGAUCCGCCCACCUCGGCCUCCCAAAGUGCUGGGAUUACAGGCGUGAGCCACCACCCCCAGCCCCUGUUUUGUUUUUGUUUUGCUUGCUUCUUAGGGUUGUUUUUCUAUUUAUGGUAAAGGCAUUGGCUUUCCAUUUGUAGCAUCAAUAGAAUAUUUCCUGUUUACAAUAACCUUAUGUCAUAGUAAAUGGUAAAGGGAUUUAAAGCAGUGGUUUUCAGCUGCCAGAGGCCUGAGUUUGGGCACACUCUGUGUGAUCGGGCAGAAGGCCUGUGGGAAGUUUAGCUGAGGACAGGGCCAGGAAAGGUGAUGGACAGUGGGGGUCUGUCCUGGUCACCAGGCCCCUGGGUCCUGCCCACCUGCUUGGAGCUCCCCACCCAUCACACAUGAUGCUGCCAAGCCCUCUGGGUAUUGUGGGCAAAUACCUUAGGAGAGAAGCUGAUGAACUUUGUUUCUUGAAAUGCACAGAUUCCUUGGACGUCCCUGAGAGCUCAGUCAUGAAAGUCAGCUUGGUUUUCUCCCCCUCAUUUGGGUUCAGAAUUUAAAGUCCACACACACGGGCAGUAAGAUGAUAUAGAUAAGGACAUCAUCACUCGGUUUCGGAUGUUAAAAUGUCUAGGUGGGUUAGGGGUGAUUUGAGAUCACACAACCUUGUGCCACAAAGAGGAAUUCCCAGGCCAGAGGGAGACAUUUUAUUGCCAUGUUAUGAUCUCAUCAUUGAGUUGAAAGGCAAUCUUGUUUCAUUUUGGAUUCUUUCUUAUGUUUAUGUCUUAUAAGGGCACUUUGAAUUUCCAAGCAAAUAAUAAUUUUGAAUUAGCUUUUAAUCAUUGACUUCUAGCACAGUUUUAUGAUCAGAAACAUGCUGUGUGAUUUGAUUGCUCUCAAAUAUAUUGAGAUUUGCUGGAACAAAAUAAGUCAGGUUAAUUUUUGUAAAUGUACCAUGCAUGCUUAAAAUGAAUGUAUGUACAUUUGUUCCUGAGAUACAGGUUGAUGGACGGAUGGCUACAUGGAUGUGAUGGAGAUGGUUUACUAUCGGGACCUUCCGCAUCCUGCUGAUGUUUUGUUGCUUAGGAUAUGAAUGGCUGAGCGGAGGCUGUAAAACCUGGCACUCUGCUUGGGUUAUCAAUACUCUGGCUGACCAUCGUCAUCGUGGGACUGACUUUGGUGGAAGUCCUUGGUUACUUAUCAUUACUGUGUUUCUGAGAAGUUAUAAAUUUGCCAUCUCCCUCUGCACAAGUUACCUUUGUGUGUCUUUCCUGAAGACUAUCUUCCCGUCUCAAAAUGGACAUGAUGGAUCCACGGAUGUACAGCAGAGAGCCAGGAGGUCCAACUGCCGUAGACAGGAAGGAAUUAAAAUUGUCCUGGAAGACAUCUUUACUUUAUGGAGACAGGUGGAAACCAAAGUUCGAGCUAAAAUCCGUAAGAUGAAGGUGACAACAAAAGUCAACCGUCAUGACAAAAUCAAUGGAAAGAGGAAGACCGCCAAAGAACAUCUGAGGAAACUAAGCAUGAAAGAACGUGAGCACGGAGAAAAGGAGAGGCAGGUGUCAGAGGCAGAGGAAAAUGGGAAAUUGGAUAUGAAAGAAAUACACACCUACAUGGAAAUGUUUCAACGUGCGCAAGCGUUGCGGCGGCGGGCAGAGGACUACUACAGAUGCAAAAUCACCCCUUCUGCAAGAAAGCCUCUUUGCAACCGGGUCAGAAUGGCGGCAGUGGAGCAUCGUCAUUCUUCAGGAUUGCCCUACUGGCCCUACCUCACAGCUGAAACUUUAAAAAACAGGAUGGGCCACCAGCCACCUCCUCCAACUCAACAACAUUCUAUAAUUGAUAACUCCCUGAGCCUCAAGACACCUUCCGAGUGUGUGCUCUAUCCCCUUCCACCCUCAGCGGAUGAUAAUCUCAAGACACCUCCCGAGUGUCUGCUCACUCCCCUUCCACCCUCAGCUCUACCCUCAGCGGAUGAUAAUCUCAAGACACCUGCCGAGUGCCUGCUCUAUCCCCUUCCACCCUCAGCGGAUGAUAAUCUCAAGACACCUCCCGAGUGUCUGCUCACUCCCCUUCCACCCUCAGCUCCACCCUCAGCGGAUGAUAAUCUCAAGACACCUCCUGAGUGUGUCUGCUCACUCCCCUUCCACCCUCAGCGGAUGAUAAUCUCAAGAAACUAAGGAAGAAUAAAUAAAUAAUAUAAAAAUAAAA